GUUUCCUUCUUGAUCCUUCACAAGGGAAGAUUUUCUUUUUUAGAGGUACAGAUUCCUCUUAGUCAAGUCCUGAUUAAAACUCCAGCUAAGACAUUAGUAAGCCUUGGUUAGUGAAGUGGCAUCAGGAAGUGCCUACAUUUUCAUGGCCUGGUAGCGUUCAGUGAAAAUGUUCAUUAACAGACACAGGCCAUUCAGUCCCGAAUCCCAAGACACUGAAGACUCUGUUUGAAUCAGACUCACGGGUUCCUUCCUAGCCACUCUCAGGGACAGGAAUGCUUCUGGUGAAGAAGUUUUCGGUGGUGGUUCAUGGAGCUUCCCUACACCAACUUGGAAAUGGCAUUCAUUUUAUUGGCUUUUGUUAUCUUUUCCUUAUUUACCCUGGCUUCCAUCUACACUACUCCGGAUGACAGUAAUGAAGAGGAAGAACAUGAAAAAAAGGGAAGGGAAAAGAAAAGGAAAAAGUCUGAAAAGAAGAAAAAUUGCUCAGAGGAAGAGCACAGAAUUGAAGCUGUUGAGCUAUGAUCUCAUAGCCACCGAUAUUUCUCGCUAAGAAGACAGAGGAAGCAAUCCAUGGGAACUACUUAUCCACAGUUACACAAGAGGAGGGGAUAAUGAAGAAAGUUAAAAUCACUUACUGAUUAAACACGAUGAUAAUAACCAUUAAUGAACUCAAUACUCGGGAAAGGCUUCACAUUUCUGGGACUCAGCAUUAUCCAAAAUAUCUAUUAAGAGCCAUACACCAUUCUAGCUGCAAUUGAUUAUACAAAAAAAAAAAGACCAAAGUGGUUACAAUAAUAAAAUAGAACACAGAGAAAGAAGAAAACUACAUGUGUUACAAUUUGGUAAGAUAAACAAACAAACAAAAAAUUUAAUCACUUUUUUUGGUCCUGCGACACACAUGAUAAUUUUUGUCUUAAUUCUCCUAACAAAUGAUAAUGAAAAGCUAUAAGUAACUGUGUUAUUGCUUCCGUAUCUGAAAUAGGUGAAAGAGGGAAAAAACACUAUAUAUUUUUUCAGCUUUACAGAAGAAAUUUUGAAAGGUUUACAUUCAAUGGAAAUAUUAGCAUUGCCUCAGUAAGCUUUAAAACACAAAUGUCUACGUUUUCUGAAGCAAUAUGGUUUACAGAGACAUGAGUGUUUGUAAAUCUCUCGUCCCAAUACUAUGUAAAUCCUUAAUGUGUAAGCAUCCAGGAAAAUUUGUCAUUCUGUGUCCUUUAUUCAUCCUAAAAGUUGAAAGUUUUCUGUUAUUUAUAUUUUUUUUUUUUUAAUUUGAGAGAGAGGCUGGGUGCAGUGGCUCACGCCUGUAAUCCCAGCACUUUGGGAGGCCGAGGUGGGCAGAUCACGAGGUCAGGAGAUUGAGACCAUCCUAGCUAACACAGUGAAACCCCGUCUCUACUAAAAAUACAAAAAAUUAGCCGAGCGUGGUGGCGGGCGCCUAUAGUCCCAUCUUCUCGGGAAGCUGAGGCAGGAGAAUGGUGUGAACCCGGGAGGCGGAGGUUGCAAUGAGCUGAGAUCAUGCCACUGCACUCCAGCCUGGGCGACAGAGCAAGACUCUGUCUCAAAAGAAAAAAAACAAAGAGAGAGAGAGGGUCUCGCUUUGUCACCGAGGCUGGAGUGCAGUGGUGUAAUCAUAGCUCACUGCAACCUUAAGUUCCUGGGCUCAGGUGAUCCUCUUGCUUCAGCCUCCCAAGUAACUGUGACUACAAGCAUGUGUCAUCACAGCCAGCUAAUUUUUGUAAUUGUUUGUAGAACCAAGGCCUCUCUAUGUUGCCUAGGCUGGUCUCCAAAUCCUGGACUCAAGCGAUCCUCUGCCUUAGCCUCCCAAAGCACUGGGAUUACACGCAUGAGCCACCAUGCCUGGCCUGUUAUUUAUAACUCUUACAAACAUUAAACCAUCACAAUCAAUGCUGGCAGCAUUAUCGUGGCAGGAAGGAAUCCACAAUACAACCAAAGAUACCUACCUGCAUCUCAUAAGAAUCAUAGCUCAGGUCUCCAUUGCCACAGAGUUUCAGUCAUGUGAGAGACUCCCUUUAUCUGUACUUACCCCUUACUGCUCACUUUCAAGAAAGAUUCAAUAAAGAUGGCUUUCUGCCAUACAGAGAUAGGCAUACUAGUGUAAACAGAAUGCUUACAAAGUUAACCAAGUAGUCACCCAGGUCAGAGUACUAAACAUUUAAAAGGGCUCACUAAGUUAGAGAGGACAGAGAAUGGGCUUUGGAGAUGAGCAGAUCUGGGUUUGAGUCUGCUCCAACCUUUCCUUAUUAUAUGACCUUGGGCAAAGUACUUAAUUUCUCUGAGCCUUGGUGUUCUCUCUGAAAAAAUGAGCAUUUUAAAAAAUCUUUGCUGGGCUGACAAAUGGAUGAGAGAUAGUAUAAGUAAAAUGUGUAACUCAGUGCCUAGGAUCGUUGCUGAAUAACGCUACCUAUUAUUAUUGGAAAGCAUUUUGGGACAUUUGGACUUUUAAGUUUACUGAUACGUUUUUUCAGAAAAGCAGAAAAAUCAACAACAUGGUUUCAAAUACUUGGAUGAGGCUCCAUUCACUCCCUUAGCCCAUCUUACAUAUAUUACUGCAUUGACUGGAAAUGGGAGGCACUUCACAAUUAGGAAUAUUGUCAGGUCAGCCAGGCGCCGUGGGCAUGCUUAUAGUCCAAGCUACUCACAAGGCUGAGGCAGGAGGAUCGCUUGAGCCUGGGAGUUUGAGGCUGCAGUGAGCUCCAGCCUGGGUGAAAGAGAAGACCCUAUCUCAAAAAAUAAAAAAUUUUAAAAACCUGUCAAGUUAGAUGUUAAAGAGGACAUGUAAAAUAAAAUCUCCCUAACAUGUUUAUGAAAUAGCUGCAAAAGGCUGAGCGUGGUGGCUCACGUCUGAAAUCCCAGCACUUUGUGAAGCCGAGGUGGGUGGAUCACCUGAGGUCAAGAGUUAGAGACCAGCCUGGCCAAGAUGGUGAAACCUCCUCUCUACUAAAAAUACAAAAAUUAGCCAGGCGUGGUGGUCCAUGCCUGUAAUCCUAGCUACUCAGGAGGCUGAGGCAGGAGAAUCACUUGAACCUGGGAGGCGGAGGUUGUAGUGAGCCAAGAUUGCGCCAUUGCUCUCCAGCCUGGGGAGCAAAUGCAAAACUCCAUUUC